GUCCCGGCGCCGCGCUCGUCCGCAGAGGAGGCGGCCCGGCCCGGGCAGCUGCGGCUCGGGAUCCGUCGAGGGGAGGCCGAGCUUGCCAAGCUGGCGCCCAGCGGGGUCAUGGUGCCCGGCGCCCGCGGCGGCGGCGCACUGGCGCGGGCUGCCGGGCGGGGCCUCCUGGCUUUGCUGCUCGCGGUCUCCGCCCCGCUCCGGCUGCAGGCGGAGGAGCUGGCCAGCCAGGUCCAGGCAUUGGGGUUUAGUGGCCAGAGCUGGGAUUAUUUCGGCUCCUUAUGCCCUGUUCUUCUGGAUCCGUUUAACUAAAGGUGAUGGCUGUGGACACCUAGUGACUUAUCAGGAUAGUGGCACAAUGACAUCUAAGAAUUAUCCCGGGACCUACCCCAAUCACACUGUUUGCGAAAAGACAAUUACAGUACCAAAGGGGAAAAGACUGAUUCUGAGGUUGGGAGAUUUGGAUAUCGAAUCCCAGACCUGUGCUUCUGACUAUCUUCUCUUCACCAGCUCUUCAGAUCAAUAUGGUCCAUACUGUGGAAGUAUGACUGUUCCCAAAGAACUCUUGUUGAACACAAGUGAAGUAACCGUCCGCUUUGAGAGUGGAUCCCACAUUUCUGGCCGGGGUUUUUUGCUGACCUAUGCGAGCAGCGACCAUCCAGAUUUAAUAACAUGUUUGGAACGAGCUAGCCAUUAUUUGAAGACAGAAUACAGCAAAUUCUGCCCAGCUGGUUGUAGAGACGUAGCAGGAGACAUUUCUGGGAAUAUGGUAGAUGGAUAUAGAGAUACCUCUUUAUUGUGCAAAGCUGCCAUCCAUGCAGGAAUAAUUGCUGAUGAACUAGGUGGCCAGAUCAGUGUGCUUCAGCGCAAAGGGAUCAGUCGAUAUGAAGGGAUUCUGGCCAAUGGUGUUCUUUCGAGGGAUGGUUCCCUGUCAGACAAGCGAUUUCUGUUUACCUCCAAUGGUUGCAGCAGAUCCUUGAGUUUUGAACCUGACGGGCAAAUCAGAGCUUCUUCCUCAUGGCAGUCGGUCAAUGAGAGUGGAGACCAAGUUCACUGGUCUCCUGGCCAAGCCCGACUUCAGGACCAAGGCCCAUCAUGGGCUUCGGGCGACAGUAGCAACAACCACAAACCACGAGAGUGGCUGGAGAUCGAUUUGGGGGAGAAAAAGAAAAUAACAGGAAUUAGGACCACAGGAUCUACACAGUCGAACUUCAACUUUUAUGUUAAGAGUUUUGUGAUGAACUUCAAAAACAAUAAUUCUAAGUGGAAGACCUAUAAAGGAAUUGUGAAUAAUGAAGAAAAGGUGUUUCAGGGUAACUCUAACUUUCGGGACCCAGUGCAAAACAAUUUCAUCCCUCCCAUCGUGGCCAGAUAUGUGCGGGUUGUCCCCCAGACAUGGCACCAGAGGAUAGCCUUGAAGGUGGAGCUCAUUGGUUGCCAGAUUACACAAGGUAAUGAUUCAUUGGUGUGGCGCAAGACAAGUCAAAGCACCAGUGUUUCAACUAAGAAAGAAGAUGAGACAAUCACAAGGCCCAUCCCCUCGGAAGAAACAUCCACAGGAAUAAACAUUACAACGGUGGCUAUUCCAUUGGUGCUCCUUGUUGUCCUGGUGUUUGCUGGAAUGGGGAUCUUUGCAGCCUUUAGAAAGAAGAAGAAGAAAGGAAGUCCGUAUGGAUCAGCAGAGGCUCAGAAAACAGACUGUUGGAAGCAGAUUAAAUAUCCCUUUGCCAGACAUCAGUCAGCUGAGUUUACCAUCAGCUAUGAUAAUGAGAAGGAGAUGACACAAAAGUUAGAUCUCAUCACAAGUGAUAUGGCAGCUUCUCCAGAGCCAGUUUCAGAGCCACUUCCUCCCUGAAGUAUGUCCCCAUGCCCCAGGACGUCGUCGUCGCCCCCAUCUCUGAGAAGACCCUGCGAAGCUUCCUGAGCAGGCGGUGCGGUUGUGUACUGCCUGCGGGUGGCUUCUGUGGCUUUCACAUCAGGGUUUUCCGCAGUGCCUGGGACACCUGAGGGCACCCGGGGGGAAAGUCAGUCACCACGACCUGAAGCAGAGUAUCCCCGUCUGCCACUGACAGGCCGGCCCGUGUGUGGUGCCCGCUAGCUGCCAUCUGUCUUGUGGUUUCAGAUUACCAGCAGCCCCUCAUGAUUGGCACCGGGACAGUCACGAGGAAGGGCUCCACCUUCCGGCCCAUGGACACGGAUGCCGAGGAGGCAGGGGUGAGCACCGAUGCCGGCGGCCACUAUGACUGCCCGCAGCGGGCCGGCCGCCACGAGUACGCGCUGCCCCUGGCGCCCCCGGAGCCCGAGUACGCCACGCCCAUCGUGGAGCGGCACGUGCUGCGCGCCCACACGUUCUCUGCGCAGAGCGGCUACCGCGUCCCAGGGCCCCAGCCCGGCCACAAACACUCCCUCUCCUCGGGCGGCUUCUCCCCCGUAGCGGGUGUGGGCGCCCAGGACGGAGACUAUCAAAGGCCACACAGCGCACAGCCUGCGGACAGGGGCUACGACCGGCCCAAAGCUGUCAGCGCCCUCGCCACCGAAAGCGGGCACCCUGACUCUCAGAAGCCCCCAACGCAUCCCGGGACGAGUGACAGCUAUUCUGCCCCCAGAGACUGCCUCACACCCCUCAACCAGACGGCCAUGACUGCCCUUUUGUGAACACAAUGUGAAAGAAGCCUGCUGUGGUACUGAGCGUCGGGCUGUCACAAGGCACUGGAAGAAGGGAGCCUGCUGGUCCAGAGUGUGCGUGUGUAUCGGUGUGUGUGUACACUUGCAUGUGUGUGUGUGAUCCAGUAGGAUCCUAGAGACAACCUGUCAUACUGUUUACAAAAUUGUGCAGCUGGUUUCGUGCUGACCCUUAGGGUGCGUCUGUUGGGUUUUGUUGGGCUAGAAAAAUGAAAAUUUUCAGAUGGCGUUUUCAUUCCUCUGACUGAUAUUGAGCUGCUUUGGUGUUAAAGGUGUAAUGUGUACAGAGUUGUAUUUAACAAUAAUAAAAGUAACUUAAGUUUGCUCUAUCAGAUUUUAGUUCUGCACAGAGGUUAAGUGGGAAAAUGCAGCUGUUGCAAAAUGUAUAUAAAUAGUAUGUUCAUUUUUUUCAGUAUAUUAUCUGAUACUGUGUUAGCAGCAGGUCUGCUUAAACCUAGUCUUGUUGUUAUUGAGUCAUUUCCUCUCCUUUGAUAACUAGAACUGAAAGCAUUUUUAACAUUCUUCUCCUGGAAGAAAUGAAUUACUUGAAGCAUGAAAAGCACACCAGGGUGGUUGUUUAUUUAGCAAUUAUGACUGUAGAUUUAAAAACAAGCAAAGAAACAACACCUCAGCAGCUGCCCGUUUCCUUAGUCUCCACUUCAGAGGGGGAUGCGAAGAGGUCGGCCCAGCUCCGGUGACCAUGAAGGUGGCACAGGAAUUACAGUGUGAAUGGCUGUGUCAGAUGUUUUCGUACCUCAGAUUAAAAAUAUUGCUGAGGUCAGACGCCACAAUUUUCAUGACUUUCUUCAGAAGUAGCACAUUUUCGUGACUUCCGCUGUCCUCUGAAAAACAAAGUUAUUUGGAACAUGUUCAUGCAAAAGUGAUUCUGACCAAGUCUAAAUCGAGCUUUUCUACUGACAUGAAACUGUUGGAAACUGAUCUCAUUUUAUAAGAAAUGAUUUUCCCCUCAAGGAGGCGUCUGUAAUUCCAGAACAGUCCAGACAUCAGCUGUACCUCAUGCUCAGUAGUUUUUAUUUGAGUUUCUUUUGUGAGUUAACUAUGGGAGAUUUAACCUCUUUUGCCAAAGAGGGAAGUGUGUGUGUUUUUUUAAUAGAAAAUAUGGACCAAAAAUUUUUUUCCCUGAAGAAUGUAUUAUAACCCUAUUUGUGUGGUUAUUACAUCCUGUGAAAUGUAUAUAUGUUAAAAUAAUGGGGGUGCUGGAAGGUCAUGGCAGACUAGCUGCUGGUUAGUGUGGAGGGGAAAUGGUUUACUUUGUAGAGUUUACAUGGUUUUAUGCGCACACUAAUUGUAAUAAACUAUGCCAAACCAAA